CCUCUUCCGGGGACGUUGUCUGCAGGUAUGGAUGUUGUUCUCUUUUCCCUGUCUUUAUUUCCUUACCAAUCGGCUGCCAUCCGAGGAGCUGAGGAAGCCUAGAGCUCUCAGAAGCAGUCCUUUGAGCUGGUGUAGGGGCACUCAGAAUGGUCCAGCGUUUGACAUACCGACGUAGGCUUUCCUACAAUACAGCCUCUAACAAAACUAGGCUGUCCCGAACCCCUGGUAAUAGAAUUGUUUACCUUUAUACCAAGAAGGUUGGGAAAGCACCAAAAUCUGCAUGUGGUGUGUGCCCAGGCAGACUUCGAGGGGUUCGUGCUGUAAGACCUAAAGUUCUUAUGAGAUUGUCCAAAACAAAGAAACAUGUCAGCAGGGCCUAUGGUGGUUCCAUGUGUGCUAAAUGUGUUCGUGACAGGAUCAAGCGUGCUUUCCUUAUCGAGGAGCAGAAAAUCGUUGUGAAAGUGUUGAAGGCACAAGCACAGAGUCAGAAAGCUAAAUAAAAAAAUGAAACUUUUUUGAGUAAUAAAAAUGAAAAGACGCUGUCCAAUAGAAAAAGUUGGUGUGCUGGAGCUACCUCACCUCAGCUUGAGAGAGCCAGUUGUGUGCAUCUCUUUCCAGUUUUGCAUCCAGUGACGUCUGCUUGGCAUCUUGAGAUUGUUAUGGUGAGAGUAUUUACACCUCAGCAAAUGCUGCAAAAUCCUGUUUUCCCCCAGAGAGCUGGAGGUUAAAUACUACCAGCACAUCCCUAGAUACUACUCAAGUUACAGUAUAUGAUCACUAAUAUAGUAUGCUCUUGGUACCAGGAGCUCUGAUAUAUAUCUGGUACAUGUUUGAUAAUGACUUGAUUGUUAUUAUAAGUACUUAUUAAUACUUCGAUUCUGUAAAGAGUUUAGGGUUUGAUUUUAUAAAAUCCAAAAUGAGCCUUUUAUUGAAUCCAGUUCUCUAUGUGACCAGUUCUCUGUAUGAAUGGAAGGGAAAAGAAUUAAAAAUCUUGCAAAGGGGAAA